CUAUCCCCCGCCCCCAGGUGGCUACCCACCAGCUGCACCAGGUAAGAGGGUCUGGGGUGGGGAGGAGAGUGAAUGCUGCCUCUGUACAGUGGCUGGGAGUGGAGAGGGGAGAACAGUAGUUUCCUCACUCCCCUCCUCCCCUCACAGCACGGCCCAGCAGGGGAGGAGAGGACAACAGGAGUAGUGGGACAGCCAGCCGAGGCAGGGGCUGGAGAAGAGCAUGACACUAAGGCCAUCGGAGGCCUAGGUUUGAAACUGCCUCCAGAAAGCCCUGGACCAGGCCCAGGGCUGGGUCUCUUGCCUUACUCUCUAGUAACAGUGGGCAAAUGCUGUCACUUUGAGACUCAGUUUUCUUCUCCGCAAAAUUGCUUCAAGGAUUUCUCCCUCAUUAGGUGGUCCUGGAUACUGAUGAGAUAGGCAGGCAGAGCGACACGGUGUCCUCCAAAGCAUUGCUAGGUGAUGGUUGCCCCUUACCACCUCUCCUACCCUCUGCUCAAGGUGUGUGGGUUUGCAGCAACAAGAUCCCCCUUGCCAAGAGAGGAAGUGGAGGCAGAUGCUAAGGGUCAAAGGUCACUCCCUGUUUUCUGCAGGAGCUGUGGGUAGUCACAUGGAGAAGUCGUCUUCUCUGGCCCUGGCCCCUUUUGGUCCUCAAAUGAGAUUUGGUCCCCACUGUGGGAAAGGAAAUAUGAGGGCUCAUGAGACCAAGGGGAGAAAAGGGUCAUUCCAAGGCUGGUCAUCCUGAGGGUGCCUGAGCCGCUGCCCCUCUCCCCAGGGGACUCCUAGGCAUCAUUGAUUUCUUUGGAGCUGAGGUCCUGUGGUUUGAACACCCCAGACCUGCAGGCCAUUUACCUUCCCUCCCAUUCAGCAGGUGAAGAACAGACUCAGACCUAGAGGUGGCUCAGCUGCUGUCCCAGGGCAUGUUAGGGGCUGAGCUGGGCCACUGCCCUCUGAAUGAGCCCACCCCAGGUUGGCUGGCACUGGCCUGGGUUCUCUCUCUAUAGUAGAAAUCCUGCCAUCCAGAUCCUGCCACUGCCACCUUUGCUAGCACAGCUGAGCAGCCUCUGAGCAGCAAGAGAGGAGGAGGCAGGAAAUUUAGGGAAGGUUCUUCCUGGAGGGUCUGGAGCCCUGGAGAUGAAGAGCCGAUCCGAAGCUGCCAUGUAGAGGAAAGCAUCUAACAGGCCAGAGGCCCCAUGAUGAUGUCGAAUGCCCAUCGGGCACCCAGCUGAGCCCUGCAGGUGUUAACUCAGUCUUCGUCACAGCAGUCUAGGCAUACACUCACCAUUAGCCCAUUUGUAAGCUGAGGAAACAAGCCUAAGGAGGGUGAAAGCCUUGCCCCAGGGCACAUACCGGUCCUGCUGGUUUCAGAGCGGGCUUUUCACCUCUGUUUCUUCCUGUCCUCUUGUGGACUGGUAUCUGUGUUUACCAUGACCCAGCCCCAUGUCCCUCCAGCCUCUUAUCCUGCUUCUCCCUGCCUUUUACAGACUUGUAAUAGCAAACAGCCAAACCCCCUCCCGCCAGUGCCUUCGCAUUACUGAAAUCUCAGAGCUCCCUAUGGUCACCUCUGUCAUGGGCUCAGCAUGGUGUCCCACAACAGUCUGUCCUUGUCUGUCCUCCUGCUCCAUGAUGGUGAACUUGGGAGGGCAGAGCCUGCCUGGGCUCUCCCAGCCUCCUUAAUACCCCACAGAGGGUCUUGGGAGUGUUUGGGGAACUCCACCUUCCUCCCUGGGAAGAGGGGAAGGUUUCCCCUCCUCUGCCAGUGGGAUAGGGGGAGACUUUCCUCCUGGUGUUUUCAUGUGGUCUGUGGUGUCCCGAGGCUCGAGGCUCGAGGCUUUACUGGGCCUCCCUUUCUGACCACCUGGGAGCUCUCAUCUCUGCCUUUCCCCGUGUGGUGGGGGACUGGCAGGGGGCUAAAGGGCUUGGUGUUGCUUUCAGGUGGUGGUCCCUGGGGAGGUGCUGCCUACCCUCCUCCGCCCAGCAUGCCCCCCAUCGGGCUGGAUAACGUGGCCACCUAUGCGGGGCAGUUCAACCAGGACUAUCUCUCGGGAAUGGCGGCCAACAUGUCUGGGACAUUUGGAGGAGCCAACAUGCCCAACCUGUACCCUGGGGCCCCUGGGGCUGGCUACCCACCAGUGCCCCCUGGCGGCUUUGGGCAGCCCCCCUCUGCCCAGCAGCCUGUUCCUCCCUAUGGGAUGUAUCCACCCCCAGGAGGAAACCCACCCUCCAGGAUGCCCUCAUAUCCGCCAUACCCAGGGGCCCCUGUGCCGGGCCAGCCCAUGCCACCCCCCGGACAGCAGCCCCCAGGGGCCUACCCUGGGCAGCCACCAGUGACCUACCCUGGUCAGCCUCCAGUGCCACUCCCUGGGCAGCAGCAGCCAGUGCCGAGCUACCCAGGAUACCCGGGGUCUGGGACUGUCACCCCCGCUGUGCCCCCAACCCAGUUUGGAAGCCGAGGCACCAUCACUGAUGCUCCCGGCUUUGACCCCCUGCGAGAUGCCGAGGUCCUGCGGAAGGCCAUGAAAGGCUUCGGGACGGAUGAGCAGGCCAUCAUUGACUGCCUGGGGAGUCGCUCCAACAAGCAGCGGCAGCAGAUCCUACUUUCCUUCAAGACGGCUUACGGCAAGGAUUUGAUCAAAGAUCUGAAAUCUGAACUGUCAGGAAACUUUGAGAAGACAAUCUUGGCUCUGAUGAAGACCCCAGUCCUCUUUGACAUUUAUGAGAUAAAGGAAGCCAUCAAGGGGGUUGGCACUGAUGAAGCCUGCCUGAUUGAGAUCCUCGCUUCCCGCAGCAAUGAGCACAUCCGAGAAUUAAACAGAGCCUACAAAGCAGAAUUCAAAAAGACCCUGGAAGAGGCCAUUCGAAGCGACACAUCAGGGCACUUCCAGCGGCUCCUCAUCUCUCUCUCUCAGGGAAACCGUGAUGAAAGCACAAACGUGGACAUGUCACUCGCCCAGAGAGAUGCCCAGGAGCUGUAUGCGGCCGGGGAGAACCGCCUGGGAACAGACGAGUCCAAGUUCAAUGCGGUUCUGUGCUCCCGGAGCCGGGCCCACCUGGUAGCAGUUUUCAAUGAGUACCAGAGAAUGACAGGCCGGGACAUUGAGAAGAGCAUCUGCCGGGAGAUGUCCGGGGACCUGGAGGAGGGCAUGCUGGCCGUGGUGAAAUGUCUCAAGAAUACCCCAGCCUUCUUUGCGGAGAGGCUCAACAAGGCCAUGAGGGGGGCAGGAACAAAGGACCGGACCCUGAUUCGCAUCAUGGUGUCUCGCAGCGAGACCGACCUCCUGGACAUCAGAUCAGAGUAUAAGCGGAUGUACGGCAAGUCGCUGUACCACGACAUCUCGGGAGAUACUUCAGGGGAUUACCGGAAGAUUCUGCUGAAGAUCUGUGGUGGCAAUGACUGAACAGUGACUGGUGGCUCACUUCUGCCCACCUGCCGGCAACACCAGUGCCAGGAAAAGGCCAAAAGAAUGUCUGUUUCUAACAAAUCCACAAAUAGCCCCGAGAUUCACCGUCCUAGAGCUUAGGCCUGUCUUCCACCCCUCCUGACCCGUAUAGUGUGCCACAGGACCUGGGUCGGUCUAGAACUCUCUCAGGAUGCCUUUUCUACCCCAUCCCUCACAGCCUCUUGCUGCUAAAAUAGAUGUUUCAUUUUUCUGACUCAUGCAAUCAUUCCCCUUUGCCUGUGGCUAAGACUUGGCUUCAUUUCGUCAUGUAAUUGUAUAUUUUUAUUUGGAGGCAUAUUUUCUUUUCUUACAGUCAUUGCCAGACAGAGGCAUACAAGUCUGUUUGCUGCAUACACAUUUCUGGUGAGGGCGACUGGGUGGGUGAAGCACCGUGUCCUCGCUGAGGAGAGAAAGGGAGGCGUGCCUGAGAAGGUAGCCUGUGCAUCUGGUGAGUGUGUCACGAGCUUUGUUACUGCCAAACUCACUCCUUUUUAGAAAAAACAAAAAAAAAGGGCCAGAAAGUCAUUCCUUCCAUCUUCCUUGCAGAAACCACGAGAACAAAGCCAGUUCCCUGUCAGUGACAGGGCUUCUUGUAAUUUGUGGUAUGUGCCUUAAACCUGAAUGUCUGUAGCCAAAACUUGUUUCCACAUUAAGAGUCAGCCAGCUCUGGAAUGGUCUGGAAAUGUCUUCCUGGUACCAACUUGUUUUCUUCUGCUUGAUUCUGCCCUGUGGCUCAGAGGUCUGGCCUUAUCAGCCAGUGAAAGUUCAUGUAACCUUACGUAGAGAUUUGUGUGCAGGAAACCCUGAGCAUACACUAGUUUGCAGGGACUCGUAAGGACAUGGGAAGGGAGGUUCCCGAAAUCCAGGCAGGAGGCCCAGACACCUGAAAGGCAAAGGGAUCUUGGUUGGUUGCAGGUGCAGUGAAGUCCACUGAAGGUGUGGUGCGAAGAAUGCAGUCCUUCACCCAGGUCCCAGGAGGGAAGAAGGGUGUGUGCUAAUUCCUGGUGCCCCUCGGCGGGGGCCAGAGAGAAGGAUGGGGACAACCCAGAGAGUCACAAGACCAGUGCCUCCCCUCAGGGUGCCUCCAGGCUGAAAGGGGCUCCUGGCUCUGGUCUCUGGGGACCCUGUGCCCGUUGGUUGGUGGUGUGAGGGAAGAGAAUCCAUAAGAGAGUUUCUGAGAAUUAUGGUGUCAUGUCCAGAAGCUAGAGCUUACCUUGCAUCAGGGGUCUCCACCCACUCCUUUUCCAACCUCCUGCGUUGAGGUUUAGAAAAGAGAGAAUCGACUAGGCACUAUGGCUCACGCCUGUAAUCCAAGGACUUUGGGAAGCUGAGGUGAGAGGAUCACUUGAGCUCAGGAGUUCAAGACUAGCCUAGCCAACAGCGAGACCCCUGUCUCUACUAAAAAAUUUGGCCAGGCGUGGUGGCUCACGGCUGUAAUCCCAGCACUUUGGGAGGUGAGGCGGGCAGAUCACCUGAGGUCAGGAGUUCGAGACCCAGCCUGGCCAACAUGGUGAAACCCCAUCUCUACUAAAAAUACAAAAAUUAGCCAGGCAUGGUGGCACAUUCCUGUAAUCCCAGCUACACAGGAUGCUGAGGCAGGAGAAUCACUUGAACCCAGGAGGCAGAGGUUGUAGUGAGCUGAGAUCACACCAUUGCACUUCAACCUGGGUGGACAGAGUGAGACUCUGUCUCAAAAAAAAAAAAAAAUUUACCUGGCAUUGUAGUGCAUUCCCUAUAGUCGGCUACUCUGGAGGCUGAGGCAGGAAGAUCCUUAGAGCCCAAGAAAUUGAGGCCGUAGUAAGCUGUGAUUACACCACUGCACUCCAGCCUGGACAACAGAGCGAGACCUUGUCUCAAAUGAGAAAAAAACAAAAAGAAAUGGGAGAAUCCAGAGAGACUAGGCUAGAUCAAGCCUGCUGGGUCCUGGCAGGAGCCCCAGGGAGUAGCUCAUCUGCAGACAUUUGCUUGAGGACUACCCCCUAAACAUAAAGGAAGAAUGACAUCCGAAGGGUGUGGAGCAGCCAUGAGCUGAGAACUAGCCUGGUCUACCUGAGAUUGAUGGCAGGUCCUGGUCAACACGUCAGCUCUGCGUCAGAGUCCAUGCCUCAAGCCCAAGCUGAAGCCCCAUCCCUGCUGCUCUCCCAAGAACUCCUCUGCUAGGGCAGGCCCCUUGCCCUUGGGUGCCAGGUGGGACCUGCCUGAUGGGAUGGGGUGCUUGGCAUAUACAACUUGCCAUGAACUCAAGGUGACCCUGGGGGCCUCCUGAAUUGUGAUGGGGCCUAGAACCAAUGUGCUCUGAUGUGACCAUAUUCUGUGACAUUACCUUGCCCUGUUUACUCCAAAGUUCCCAGCCUGGUGCCCAGCAGGCAAUAUUGCACCUACAGACACAUUUACUUUGGUUUCCAAAGUGUUUUUAGACAUUUGAAUUUGUUGCCAACAUUUAAACAUUGAGAGAUUUCAUAUUUUUAAAAAUCUGGAAUUCUGGCUUCUCUUGAAAACUCAGAAAUUCUGGCACUAUGGGGCUUGCAUUCCUGCAUGGCUGGAGCUGAGUUGCAGCUGCCCCUUUAGGCCUGUACUCCUUAUUUGCUAUAGGCUCCGUCUUGUAUUACACUAAGCCCAUGUCACCCAUUUGGCUCCUGCAGGCCUUUGGGUUUGAGACCCUGGUCUACACACUUGGAGACCACCUGUUGUAAAGUACAUGGAUGUGCUUUGGUCAAGGAAUAGACCAAGGUGGAUAUCCAGGCCAGAGUGACUCAGCGAGUUUAGGUCACAGGCGUAUACUCCACUUGUUAUAUAACCUGCUUGUGUAAGUUCAUACUUGGCUCAAAGCCACUAUUGUUUGGAAAAGGUAUAACUGCCCUGCUGACGCUGUACAGAUGUUCUUGGGCUCGGAUGGGCAUGGCUCCACGUGGUGUGCACUAGCACCCAGAGAGAGUGAAGCUAUUGACCCCUGUAAGGGAGAGUGACCAUCUGGCAGAUAGAUAGAGGGGAGCCAGGACAUGGCUCAGCUUGUGCCCAGAGGGAGAGUUAAGCCGCUGACCCUGUAGCCAGGGAGUGCACCUGCAAGCAUGGGGGUGGCAGGAGCCACAGAGCUGGCUGCUGAGAGGAGCUGCAGAUCUGGAGAAGACAGCCUAGGUAAAGGUGGACAGUGUGAGAGCUGCUGAUGAGAUAGCUGCUGAAUAAAACUACAUUUUACCUGCCUAUGGCCCGCCAGGUUUUCUUUCAGCUAUCGCCCAUCCACCCAGUCCCCUCGAACCUCAGCAUGGGCUGGAACCUGACCCUGGGCAUGACAUUUGGCAUAGUUGUGGACCUGACACCUGUGUUUGUCCUAGUCCUGUUUCUCCCUGCCUUCCUGUUCCUCUCGCUGCCCUCAUGGUCACUCCCAAGAGAUCCAACCCAUGUUAAGUAUGGGCUGGAGGACUGCAUGAAUGCCUCAUGAUCUUCCCAGAGGCAAAGGCACCUACUGCCUUCCAAGGUCAGUGGGAGGUUGGGAUCAACACUGUUUAUUAUGCUUAGGACAAAAAAGAUAGGGAGAAAGAUGUGCAACCUUACAGGUCAUCUUUCUGGGAUAGAACACAAUGGGUCUUCUCCUGCCUCCUGGAUAUGUUAGUCAAGGCCAGUCCAUGCUACACAUCUAGUCUGACUUCUAAAAUAGAAGCACCAGAUGAAUUCAGCCCUGAGAGAAUUUUCAGCAGCUGUGGGGGCGCUGGAGGAAACACUAUUAAAUAGUUUUGCACCUGAGACAGAUAGCCUCACUCGCCUCACCCUAGUCCUGGUGGCAUUUGUCUCAGGUGCAAAAUUUAAGAAAGAAACCUUGGAGUGCUCACCCUGUGGCUGGGUAGAUGGUCCUAAAGUGGUGGUUUUCAAGCCUGAGUGUGUAUCAGGAUCAUCAGGGGAGCUUGCUAAAGAGCAGUUCCUGCGGUCAGACCCUCAUGCAUUUUGAGCAGGUGUGGGGACUGGGAAACUGCAUCUGUAACCUGCUGUAAUCUAACGCUUAUCUAAAUACUACUGUGCUCACACAGAGAACACCGCAAAAGUAGAGGUGUUCCUCCAGAGGGCAGGUGAGCAGAUGGCACAGUCUGCUUGGAAUUCAGUCAGGUGAUGAGAGAUGAGAUGAGGCACUCCUAGCUUUGGGAAGAGGGAGCUGAAAGAUGAACCUUUGCAGGUGCCCACGGUCAAAGUGGUGGUUUAAUGCCAUGCCAUGCCCAUUUUCUGUUGGCCUUGGCAGGGAGUUACAGCCCUACCUUAGGACCUGGCUCCUUAUUUCUGCUGUAGGCUCUUUCCUGCCCUGGCCGAGAUGGAGUGGAAUGAGACCUAGAAACAUCAAGCUAAAUACAUGUCCUCAGAAAGAUAAAGGUUUACAUUUUCACCCCCAUCAAAUCUGAAAGCUCUCUGCCUGUGUUUUUCUAAGGGAUAGGGACAUCAUUACUCAGUCCACAACCUGGACUCAUGUAGGGUCCCCUGUCAGUAAAGGAGUCAGUCAAGCCCACCAGGUAUACCAAGGACUCUUACCCUCAGCCCCUACUCCUUGGAAAGCUGCCCCUUGGCCUAAUAUUGGUGUUUAGCUUGAGCCUGACUCCUUCUCAACACUAAGAGCUGAUGAAGUCCUGAAGCAGAAAGAGCUCUGACCUGAGAGUCAAACAUCCUUAUUCUGAUCUCAGCUCAGCCCCUGAUUUGUUGUGUGACCCUGGAUAUGUCACUUCCUGUCUUUUUGACUUUUUAAAAUGAAGGGUAGACUAGAGGAGAGCUUCUAAAACUUUAAUGUGGUCAACGAAAUGGAAUAGGAAAUUCCACAAGUCUGUCCUUCCACAAAAGCAGCAAAUAAGGUGGCAAAAACUCAAAUUUAUGGGAACUCUGGAAACGAAUUGAAAGUUUACAGCAAUCAGGUGAAUACCUAAGAAUAAAAGCUGGAUUUAGUAAGA